CUGUUCCCUCUGCUCUGGGUCUCCGCCGGCGCCCGCCCCGCCAGCCUCACCUGCGCGGCACGUGACCCGCACCGCCCGUGGGCACCUUGAAGGCGGAUCCCGCGCGCCCCCGCUCCUGCAGGCUGUUUUUCUUCAAAUAAAGAACAUGGUGAAACUGAUUCACACAUUAGCUGAUCAUGGUGACGAUGUCAACUGCUGUGCCUUCUCCUUUUCCCUCUUGGCUACUUGCUCCUUGGACAAAACAAUUCGCCUGUACUCGUUACGUGACUUUACUGAACUGCCACAUUCUCCAUUGAAGUUUCAUACCUAUGCUGUCCACUGCUGCUGUUUCUCCCCUUCAGGACAUAUUUUGGCAUCGUGUUCAACAGAUGGUACCACUGUCCUAUGGAAUACUGAAAAUGGACAGAUGCUGGCAGUGAUGGAACAGCCUAGUGGCAGCCCUGUGAGGGUUUGCCAGUUUUCCCCAGACUCCACGUGUUUGGCAUCAGGGGCAGCUGAUGGAACUGUGGUUUUGUGGAAUGCACAGUCAUACAAAUUAUAUAGAUGUGGUAGUGUUAAAGAUGGCUCCUUGGCGGCAUGUGCAUUUUCUCCUAAUGGAAGCUUCUUUGUCACUGGCUCCUCAUGUGGUGAUUUAACAGUGUGGGAUGAUAAAAUGAGGUGUCUGCAUAGUGAAAAAGCACAUGAUCUUGGAAUUACCUGCUGCGAUUUUUCUUCACAGCCAGUUUCUGAUGGAGAACAAGGUCUUCAGUUUUUUCGACUGGCAUCAUGUGGUCAGGAUUGCCAAGUCAAAAUUUGGAUUGUUUCUUUUACCCAUAUCUUAGGUUUUGAAUUAAAAUAUAAAAGUACACUGAGUGGGCACUGUGCUCCUGUUCUGGCUUGUGCUUUUUCCCAUGAUGGGCAGAUGCUAGUCUCAGGGUCAGUGGAUAAGUCUGUCAUAGUAUAUGAUACUAAUACUGAGAAUAUACUUCACACAUUGACUCAGCACACCAGGUAUGUCACAACUUGUGCUUUUGCACCUAAUACCCUUUUACUUGCUACUGGUUCAAUGGACAAAACAGUGAACAUCUGGCAAUUUGACCUGGAAACACUUUGCCAAGCAAGGCGCACAGAACAUCAGCUGAAGCAAUUUACCGAAGAUUGGUCAGAGGAGGAUGUCUCAACAUGGCUUUGUGCACAAGAUUUAAAAGAUCUUGUUGGUAUUUUCAAGAUGAAUAACAUUGAUGGAAAAGAACUGUUGAAUCUUACAAAAGAAAGUCUGGCUGAUGAUUUGAAAAUUGAAUCUCUAGGACUGCGUAGUAAAGUGCUGAGGAAAAUUGAAGAGCUCAGGACCAAGGUUAAAUCCCUUUCUUCAGGAAUUCCUGAUGAAUUUAUAUGUCCAAUAACUAGAGAACUUAUGAAAGAUCCGGUCAUCGCAUCAGCUUACCACAAGUGACUCUAUAGAAAACAUCCAGCUACUUGGGAGGCUGAGGCAGGAGAAUUGCUUGAACCCGGAAGGCAGAGGUUGCAGUGAGCCGAGAUCAUGCCACUGCACUCUAGCCCCGGCGACAAUGUGAGACUCCAUCUCAAAAAAAAAAAGAAAAAAGAAAACAUCCCCAGUCAUGUAUUUACAGGUACAUUUGUAUACAUUCCUAAUACUGAUAGGCACUGCUGUACCUUUUUAGUUAUGUCCAAUCUUUAAAAAAAUUUGGCUUGGUCAUUUUUGCCAAUUUAGCUGUCAAGAUAAUUUUUGUUUUGAGACAGAGUCUCACUGUGUCACCCAGGCUGGAAUGCAGUGACAUGAUCUCAGUUCACUGAGACCUCUACCUCCUGGGUUUAAGCGAUUCUCCUGCCUCAGCCUCCCUAGUAGCUAGGAUUAUGGGCACGUGCCACCAUGUCUGGCUAAUUUUUGUAUUUUUAGUAGAGACAGGGUUUUGCCACGUUGGCCAGGCUGGUCUUGAACUCCUGACCUCAAGUGAUGUGCCCAGCCAAGAUAAAUUUUAGAAUCAUCUUAUGUUACAACACAAAGUGGUAUUUUGGUUAGAAUUACAGAAAACCUAAAAACUAAAUGUUAACUGGGGCUAAAGAGUAGAAAUGCCUGCCCUGCACUGGUAGGUGUUCCAGCUAGAUUAUUUCUUUCAGGUCUAUUCUGAACAUAUAAAAACCUCCUAAACCUGAUCUGCCCACUCUGCUUUUUCUCUAGAGCCUUCACCGUGUUGGGUUAUACUUGGUUAUACUCUGACUUCAGGUAUGCUUUUCAGUUGCAGUUCAAGUAUACUGUCUAAUUCCUAUUUGUCAUCGUAGACUUUUCUCUUUCAUGCCUUUCACUAGUUCUGGAAAUGUUUCAGCCAUUCUCAUCCCCUGCAGCUUCUCUCUUAAGCCUUUCUAGGUGUUUUUCUUGGACCUGCCUACCAGUUGUCUUUCCUGCAGUUGUCUAACUGCUGUUUACCUGUCCAAUGAGAUUUUUUUAAAAUUUCAGUUACUAUAGUUGUCCUUUCUGGAAGUCCCGUGUACAGGGAGAGUAAGAGCAUUGUCUGUGGAGCCACACUGCUUGGGUUUAAAUCCCAGGUCAGUUGCUCCCUACCUGUGUGACCCUGGAAAGUUAUUCAGGCCAUACCUCAGUUUCCUCAUUUAUAAAAUAGGAAUGCUAACAAUAUCUUACAUCAUAAGGUUGUUGUGCAGAUUAAAGAAGUUAAUAUAGGUAAUGGUGCCCUGGAACAGUCUAAUGAUAUGCUGUUUGGCAAUAAGCACUUCAAAAGACGGUCAGUGUCAUUAAUGCCAAUCAAAACCAUGUCAUACCUGUUAAGAUGGCUAGAAUCAAAAAGUAGGAAAAUACGUGUUGGCAAGGAUGUGCAGAAAAUGGAACCUUCAUGUGUGGUUGCUGUUGAAAACAGUCUGGAAGCUCUUCAGAAAGUUAUUACAAUUCCACUCCUAAGUCUAUAGGCAGGAGAAUUGAAAA